GUCUCUCUGGGCUCUGUGUCUAAGGAGCCCUAGGGCACUGGGUGUGAGUCACUUAGGUGGGCCUGUGUGGAGGGGUGUCUGGGGAGGACAUUGAACAGGCUGGGCUGAAAGGGCGUUCGGCUGUCGGGGGAGGUCUCUGGGAAGACAGGUUCCUCACAGCAAAGCCUGUGGUGAAGGUCUCAGAGGCCUCUCAGGGGAAGUCUCAAGGUCUCCAGUAAGGGGAACGAGGUCUGGAGGGAGGAGGUUGUGGAUCCUCAGGCAGGGUUGUUGAGGGAGGGGGGUCUCCAGGUCCCCAGAAGCAGGGACCUCAGGCAGGAGUACCAGGGGAGGAGUGUGGAGGAAGCGGGCUCCUCAGCUGGGGGCCUCGGGGUAGGAAAGGCCUGGGCCCAUCCUGCCCUUGUGGCCCCCGGCUGCAGCCUCAGUGGCAUGGGGGUGAAGCGGAGCCUCCAGAGUGGGGGCAUUCUGCUCAGCCUCGUGGCCAACGUCCUCAUGGUGCUCUCCACGGCCACCAACUACUGGACCCGCCAACAAGAGGGCCACAGUGGCCUGUGGCAGGAAUGCAACCACGGCAUCUGCUCCAGCAUCCCCUGCCAGACCACGCUGGCGGUGACUGUGGCGUGCAUGGUGCUGGCGGUGGGUGUCGGCGUGGUGGGCAUGGUGAUGGGACUGCGGAUUCGGUGCGACGAGGGCGAGUCGCUGCGGGGCCAGACCACGAGCGCCUUCCUCUUCCUCGGCGCCCCCACCAGGCCCAGCUAGCUCAUCUUGCGGCUGGGCGGGGCCCAGGACUGCUGCUGCUGACCGCCUUGAUAGGCUACACCGUGAAGAAUGCGUGGAAGAACAACGUCUUCUUCUCUUGGUCCUAUUUUUCUGGGUGGCUGGCCUUACCCUUCUCAAUUCUCGCGGGUAAACUGGACAGCGGGAAGAGGGUGGAGGAGACUGCCCAGAAGACCCUCACCCCAGAGGCUCCCCAGCUGCCCUCCCAGGAAACCCCGGGGACCUCUCGGGGACUCCCCAACACACUAACGACUCCCGCAGACCCGGCAGAGACCCCCUUGGAGCCCCAAACCCCAGUCCCCGGGGCCCUCCCGGCCAUCCGCCCCAGGGCCCACCUUCCUCUCCCUGCUCCGCACCCCCGUCCCCCCAGGCUUCUGCUUUCUGCUGGCAGACAUGAUCAUGCAGAGCACCGACGCCAUCAGUGGAUUCCCCGUGUGUCUGUGACUGCAGCCUGCCUGGGGCAGAAUAAAGGAACGGCUUUUUUUAGC